GCGGCUGCGCCGGCGCGUCGAGGGGAGAGGCAGCAGCCGCGAUGGACGUGUUCCUCAUGAUCCGGCGCCACAAGACCACCAUCUUCACGGACGCCAAGGAGUCCAGCACGGUGUUCGAACUGAAGCGCAUCGUCGAGGGCAUCCUCAAGCGGCCUCCUGACGAGCAGCGGCUGUACAAGGAUGACCAACUCUUGGAUGAUGGCAAGACACUGGGCGAGUGUGGCUUCACCAGUCAAACAGCACGGCCACAGGCCCCAGCCACAGUGGGGCUGGCCUUCCGGGCAGAUGACACCUUUGAGGCCCUGUGCAUCGAGCCGUUUUCCAGCCCGCCAGAGCUGCCCGAUGUGAUGAAGCCCCAGGACUCGGGAAGCAGUGCCAAUGAACAAGCCGUGCAGUGAGGACCCCCAAGAGGCCCAUUUCCCCCAAUAAAAGAGAUUUGGGAGUCUGCCUGGUUGCUGCCUCUUUUUCCCGCCCCUCCCUGGGAUGGGUCCCACUCCCUGUGGGCUCCUUUUGGGGCUUGUGCUUGGCAGUUCCUGUGCUGUCCUGUCUCCCAGAUCCUGAGACCCUGGCUGAGAACUUGGCCCAGCCUGCUGCUUAAAGGCACCAUGGGGACCUGGGUUGCCCUGAGACCCAAGCCAUUGUUAGCAGCUAGCCAGCCACACCAACCACGCCAGGGGGAGGAAAGGGAAGGACUGGGAGAGACACAAAGACCAGAGCCAGCCUCAGGGACAAGAGAUUCCAGUUUUAGGCCUUUCUCCUUCUAAGUGCCCCCCACCCCCAUAGCCUGCAUGUCCACUCCCAGACGAUGGCCAAGAGCAGAAACACAAGCUGGAGCCAGUGUCCUGGUUUGACAGCAUGUUCAACGAGGGAACCCCAAGACGGACCCACACAGGUCCACCCACGCUGGGGGCUGUAAUCACGGAGGGAAGUGGCUGCCCCCUUAACACACCUUUAAUAAACAGUCUACAGACCCA